AGACUCGAAAACAACAUCUACUCAGAAAAGUUGUUUCUUUCCUAUCUCCUUAAACUUUCCCACUUCCACAUAUCGGAGCUUCUUCCCACCUCGGCCUACUCAAGCAUGAGAUCGGAGGCGGGAGGGCGGCGACUGGCGGCGCGAUGGACCUGACCGGGCUCCUGCUGGACGAAGAAGGCACCUUCUCCCUCGCCGGCUUCCAGGACUUCACGUUCCUCCCAGGACACCAGAAGCUGAGUGCCCGGAUCCGAAGGAGGCUCUACUAUGGCUGGGACUGGGAAGCCGACUGUAGCCUGGAGGAGCUCUCCAGCCCGGUGGCAGACAUUGCUGUCGAACUGCUCCAGAAGGCAGCCCCCAGCCCUAUUCGCCGACUCCAGAAGAAAUAUGUAGCUCAUGUGUCCCGGGAGGCAUGCAUCUCCCCAUGUGCUAUGAUGCUGGCUCUGGUGUACAUUGAACGGCUCCGGCACCGAAACCCAGACUACUUGCAGCAUGUGUCAUCCUCUGACUUGUUCCUGAUCUCCAUGAUGGUGGCCAGUAAGUACCUCUAUGAUGAAGGGGAGGAGGAGGAGGUCUUCAACGACGAAUGGGGAGCUGCUGGGGGUGUGGCCGUGCCCACUCUCAAUGCCUUGGAGAGGGGCUUCCUGAGUGCCAUGGAUUGGCAUCUCUACACUGACCCUCGGGAGAUCUUUGAGGUGCUGAGCUGGUUGGAGAGCUGUGUGGCUGAGCAGCAGGGACGGUGGCGAGGCUGGUACACCUACACAGACCUGUGUGUGCUGCUGGAGCAGCCGACCUGGCAGUUGGCCCUGGGCUCCCUCUGCCAGCGGCUGGUAAAGCUGUCUUGCCUGUUAGCUGUGGCAUAUGUGAGCAGUGUGGCCCUGGCUGUGGCAUCGGUGGCCGUAAUACAUCAGUCUUUGGGGCUGUCCUGCAUCCCUACACCUGGGCCGCCUGACCUUGGACUGACCUCCCGUUGCCUCCUGGAGCCCUGCAUACCUUCUGUGCCACAAUGCCUGCCGUCUCUCGCUAAUGUCUCCAGCUGCCUGGAAGGCAGCAUGGGGCUGCGGUCACUCUGGGGCAGUCUUCUGGCCUCACUGACUCCUCCACCAUUGCCUCCCCCAGACCCCCCUGCCCCUCCCACUCUUCUUCAUAACUGCCACCUUUGCCAGAAGCUCCAGAGAGACUCCCCAACCUGCCAUGCCUGCCUCCACCCCAACCGUACAGUCCCCACUGCGCUGUCCAGCCCCUGGUACCAUACCUAUGGCCUGGCUCCCCCCUGGCCUUGGAGCCCGGUGCUCCUUUCACUUCCUCAGCCUCAGCAAUGUUCCCUUUUCAGUGUCAUGGAGCUGGCUCGCCUCAAGUCUUUCGUUUUCCCAGGCUAGGUAGGGCUGUGAGGAAUGCAUUAAGAGGGUUUGGGAGUUUCUGAGAACCUGGAGGAGCAAAGCUUGAUUCAGAUCCUGUCUGCCUCGCUGGGUCCUUGGCAGGUCCCCUGUCCUCCUGGGUGGGAGCUUAUGGGGUGGUGGGGCAGAAGGACUGAAGGUAAUUCACUCCUAGAUCGCAGUGGCUGGCUGCUUGGCCAGGACAGUGAUGCCGCCAGGGAGAGCUUCCGCUUGGUGACCAGGGACAUGUCCCAGAUGGACAUAGAAGCCCCUCUCUGCCUCCCUGGGAUUUUUUAGACUUUUACUUUUGAUUUCCCUAGGAUGGAAGAGUAUAGGUGGGAGAUAAGGGAAGUGGGGUGAGAGGAGAAAGGAAAUGUUGGCAUGGGCCUGUGUGAUGUCCCUGAGGCAGAAGAGCCGGGGACUGAUGGGUUCAGGUGGGAGCUGCUGGGUGAGGCAGGGAACCCUUUUCACUCCCAUUCCUUAGCUUUAGUCUAAUGGAGCCAAGGACUGCUGGGACCUUCAACCCUGAUCUUUUGUCUUCCAGUCUUCUCUUAGUGUCCUGCUCCUAGGUUUCCCUCUCUUCUGGUUCUUCUCCCAGGUAUUCUCUUCCCAGGCCUCUCUGGCCACUGCUUUGUAUCAGGGUUUUUCACGCUUUUGUAGAACUGAGGUUUCAAUAAACAGUUUCAGUUGCA